UAUGCCAUGGCUGUGAUGAACCACCAUGUAUGCCCUGUGGAGAACUGGUAUGAAGGACUCUGCAGACAACCUUGCUCUAAAGCUUCCUUCAUCUCUGUCCCCUCUUGGGCCUGAGGCUGCCACGAGCCAGACUGCAACCCUGAGCCUCACUGCUCUUCUCUGAAAUUGGUCCCCAGGCAUGGCUUCUUGCCACCUACCCACUUCCCACUAUCCCUUUGCCCCUUUGGUUACUGCUUCAGGCGGGCACUGGGGAGUGGGAUCUUCUGUCCCUGUAGGGGAGGUCUGGGAGAGAGUCCUCUUUGAGGCCUGAGGCUAUAGGCCAAGGGCCUGGGGGCAGUCCCUUCCCCCAGUCUACUCCCUGUCCUGCCUGCCAGGUCCUACAACGAGUCCUGCCCUCCUGACCCUGCUGAGCAAGGGGGUCCCAAGACCUGCUGCACCCUGGACGAUGUCCCCCUCAUCAGGUGAGGAAACAGGCUCAGUCUUCCUCAUCCAGGUCACACAGCUAAUAAGCGGAGGCACCUGGAUUUAAGCUGGAGCCCUCAGAUUGCCCAGCCCGUGUUCUGGCUCAAGGAUAGCCAAACCAGCCGCAGGGCUCAGCAAAGAGUGUCAGGGUUGCCCGAACACUCCUGGGCACUCCCUUCUCUCUCACACACAUGAGCUCUGCUUUGGGGGCCCAGCCUGGAACCAGUUGUUCAUGAGGGACCCUGGAUCUUCACAUAAAUCAGUGGCCUGCCUGCUAAGGAGCAGGUGCAGCAAGUGUGGCUCCUAUCCCCCAGAAAGCUGCCUCUUCAGCCUCAUUGGCAACAUGGGUGCUUUCAUGGUGGCCCUGAUCUGCCUCCUGCGCUACGGGCAGCUCCUGGAGCAGAGUCGGCACUCUUGGGUUAACACCACGGCACUCAUCACAGGCUGCACCAACGCUGCGGGCCUCUUGGUGGUUGGCAACUUUCAGGUGGAUCAUGCCAGGUCUCUGCACUACGUUGGAGCUGGCGUGGCCUUCCCUGCGGGGCUGCUCUUUGUUUGCCUGCACUGUGCUCUCUCCUACCAAGGGGCCACCGCCCCGCUGGACCUGGCUGUGGCCUAUCUGCGAAGUGUGCUGGCUGUCAUCGCCUUUAUCACCCUGGUCCUCAGUGGAGUCUUCUUUGUCCAUGAGAGUUCUCAGCUGCAACAUGGGGCAGCCCUGUGUGAGUGGGUGUGUGUCAUCGAUAUCCUCAUUUUCUAUGGCACCUUCAGCUACGAGUUUGGGGCAGUCUCCUCAGACACACUGGUGGCUGCACUGCAGCCUACCCCUGGCCGGGCCUGCAAGUCCUCCGGGAGCAGCAGCACCUCCACCCACCUCAACUGUGCCCCCGAGAGCAUCGCUAUGAUCUAAGGUCUGGGGAGGGUGGCUGGCCCGGCCUCCACAGCACCCCACCCCAUAUCUUCUUUCCAUUUAUUUCGUACCAAAAACAAUUUUGAGAAAGUAUUCUGUUGGGAUCUGGGCUUCCUCACUUCUGGAGAAGUGGCCAUCCCAUGCCCACCUGUGCCAUGGAGGAGUGGGCCCUGCCAGCUGCCACAGCUGCAUGACCUGCUUCCCCACCCCACGGUGUCGUUUUGUUUUUAAAGGUCACCUGUCCUCACUCACCCAGCCAGCCCUUCAGGUGCCUUCUACUCCCAGUGCCAAAGCCAGACCACUGGGGUUUCCUGCUGCAGGAAUUGGGGGCUGGGAACAGCAGAGGGGAUAGAAGUCUGGUGGAGGUGGAGUGGGCACGCCUUAGCCUACGGAAAGGCCCAUUUCUGGGCCCACUGAGCUGCACUGGGAUUCUUCACUCUGCCCCUCACUUCCUUUAGGGCAAAUAACACAGCAGAACCACGUGGGUAUUUUAGUACUUUUUUUUAUAUUAAAAGAAUUCUAAUUUGCA